CUUUUUCUGGGGCCGCUCCAGCUGGUGCCGGCCACCUCCACUCCCCUUUGCUUCUUGCUGUCCCUAAGGUCGGAUGGGGACAGGCUGGGGCCACCAGCCAGCUCCAUGGACAGGGACUUUGCCUCUGCUCACCUUCCAGCUGUGGAAAGAAAAGAAGAAACGCCUGUGUUGAUUUCCAUUUGGAAGAUCCUUCCUCCUCCUAAACUUCCAGGGGCAGACAAAGUGAUUCGAUCUUGGAUUGACUGUAGAAGAAGGGACAGAAAGAGCCCAGAACAUUCCCCCAGAUGUUCCAACUGUGACUUCUCCCUGGCGCCUUGAUGGGAGCAUCUGAAACACCCUUCACCAUCUAGAUGCACAAGGAAGCAGAGAUGCUAAUUGGUCCCCAGCUGGAUGAGAAGCGCUGGGGGUGGAGGUUGGGAGAUGGGAGUGCUGCCCCUCCCUUCCUCCCCCAAGCCCUGUCUUUCCUUCUCCUCCUGCCACUGGCAUCGUGCUCAGAACUGCAUGAUGAAGAAGAGUGUGGCUGUCUGGGUAGUCUCUCAGCUCUACCCUUGAUUUGCUACGUGGCCCUGACCAGCGCCCUACAGCCCACUCCACUGCCCUUUCAAGAGCUGAGGCUGGUGGGGGGCCCCAGCCGCUGCCGGGGCCGCCUGGAAGUCAUGCACGGUGGCUCCUGGGGCAGCGUCUGUGAUGACGACUGGGACGUGGUGGACGCCAACGUAGUGUGUCGCCAGCUGGGCUGUGGCCUGGCACUGCCCGUGCCACGGCCCCUUGCCUUUGGCCAAGGCCGAGGCCCCAUCCUGCUGGACAACGUGGAGUGCCGCGGGCAGGAAGCUGCGCUGAGCGAGUGCGGCAGCCGCGGCUGGGGCGUCCACAAUUGCUUUCACUACGAGGAUGUGGCUGUCCUGUGUGAUGAAUUCUUGCCAACGCAGCCCCCAACAAGGAAGAUGUUAACCAGUAGAGCACCUCCUACGACACUGCCGAAUGGAAAAAGUGAGGGCAGCGUACGCCUGGUAGGGGGCGCGAACCUGUGUCAGGGCCGAGUGGAGAUCCUGCACAGUGGCCUGUGGGGCACCGUGUGUGACGACGACUGGGGGCUGCCGGAUGCCGCUGUGGUCUGUCGUCAGCUGGGCUGCGGGGCGGCCAUGGCCGCCACCACCAACGCCUUCUUCGGCUAUGGCACCGGACACAUCCUGCUGGACAACGUGCACUGCGAAGGCGGCGAGCCCCGCCUGGCAGCCUGCCAGAGCCUGGGCUGGGGUGUGCACAACUGCGGCCACCACGAGGACGCGGGCGCGCUCUGCGCAGGCCUGGGUCCCCCAACGCUCACAGCACUGCCAUCCUCAGCCACAAGAGAGGACUGGGCUUGGCAGACAGAUCCGUCCGCUACAGGAGUUGGCCCCCAGCCUUCCCGGGAGACAGCACUGCUCACCACCGCCGCCUGGGCCGCGGGGAAGAAAAGUGGACGGCUGCGACUGGUGGGCGGCCCGGGUCCGUGCCGCGGCCGCGUGGAGGUGUUGCACGCCGGGGGCUGGGGCACCGUGUGCGACGAUGACUGGGACUUUGCGGACGCGCGCGUGGCCUGCCGCGAAGCGGGCUGCGGGCCUGCGCUGGGCGCUACGGGACUGGGCCACUUCGGCUACGGCCGCGGCCCCGUGCUGCUGGACAACGUGGGCUGCGCCGGCACCGAGGCUCGCCUGAGCGACUGCUUCCACCUGGGCUGGGGCCAGCACAACUGCGGCCACCACGAGGACGCGGGAGCGCUCUGCGCAGGCCCAGAGGAGCUGGGACUGCAAGUCCAGCAGGAUGGUUCUGAGACCACGCGGGUGCCCACUCCUCGGCCCAGGGACGGGCAUCUACGUCUGGUCAAUGGAGCCCACCGAUGCGAGGGACGUGUAGAGCUCUACCUAGGGCAACGGUGGGGCACUGUCUGUGAUGAUGCUUGGGACCUGCGGGCAGCCGGUGUCCUGUGCCGCCAGCUGGGCUGUGGCCAGGCCCUCGCAGCCCCUGGCGAGGCUCACUUUGGCCCAGGCCGAGGCCCCAUUCUCCUGGACAAUGUCAAGUGCCGUGGGGAAGAAAGUGCUCUGCUGCUCUGCUCUCAUAUCCGCUGGGAUGCCCACAACUGUGACCACAGCGAGGAUGCCAGUGUCCUGUGCCAGCCUUCAUGACCCAGCCCGCUCUGCAGACCACCUCUUCUUCUGGGAGCUGUGACCUCCCUUCCUCCUCCAGGAAGCCCUCCUCUUGUGAUGACUACAGUUCACUUUGCCCCUCCUUCCCUUGCCUGGGAGAGAGCCUACCUAGACAGUGCAGUCCUGCUUGGGGGAGCCUGGCUGUACCCCCGUCCACUUACUGCGUGACCUCAGCCUGUCAUCGACUGUUGUGAGCCCAAUUCAGUGAAAGCUCCUGUGGUUUUGCUCAGCCAAAACCAAAACGAGGGGAAGAGGAUGAUUCCUAACUCUUCUGUUUGGUGGGGCUCUUUUUAUAGCACCAGACUCUGCCUUCCUUGACCUAGAUCCAGGAGGCUCAGGGGCUCUUUAAAUGGGGUAUCUCCUCUUCCCCCAACCCAUCUUGGGAUCCCCAAGAAGAGGGAAGGCAGGAGGGGCCUACAGCUCCUACCUUGGGCCCUCAGGGGCUGCAGAGGAACCUGGGUCCCUGUCCUGCCCUGCUCCGCGAGGGCCUGGACUAACUCAGAUGGUGCUCGGCUGGACAAGGGGACUGGGGGAGGGGCCAAAGCAGGGACAGUGGCCCCUCCCUGCAGCUGGAACCAGCAUCUCUGAUUUAUGCCGUCUCCACCACAGAGCCUCCACUUUGCAGGAGUGAAGAACCCUGGGGGCCUGUAGCCACCAGUUCAUAGGUGCCAAGUCAAUAAAGCAUUGUCCCCCGUCUCUUA